GUGUGUAUGUGUGUGUGUGUGUGUGUGUGUGUGUAUGUAUACAGUUGACCCCUGACCAACUUGGGGGCUAGGGGUGCCAGCCCCCUGUGCAGUUGAAAAUCUGCCUGUAACUUUUGACUCCCCUAAAACUUAACUCCUAAUAGUGUUCUGUUGAUUGGACACCCUACCAAUAACAUAAACAGUCAGUUAACACAUUCAUGUUAAAUGUAUUCUAUCCUGAAUUCUGACAAUAAAGUAAGCUAGAGAAAAGAAAAUGUUAUUGAGAAAAUGCUAAGGAAGAGAAAAUACAUUUACUAGCCACUAAGUGGAGUGUAUCAUCGUAACGGGCUCCCCUGAUUGUCUUCACGUUGAGUAGGCUGUGAGCAGGAGGAGGGGGCGGUUGUCUUGCUGUCUCAGGAGUGGCAGAGGCAGGAGAAAGUCCACAUAUAAGUGGACCACACGAUUCAAACCCCUGUCCUUCAAGGGUCAAGUGUAGUCCUCCGCUGGCUGGUAAAUAGCUCACCUCAGCCCUUCCUGGGUCCCCACCACCCCCCACCCAGCCCUCCCAGCCCUCUUCUGAAACCUGCUGUUAAUUCCCAUUUCUCUGAUGAGGAAACUGAGUGGCCACAGGGUACUGUUCCUAGCGGAAAAUUGGCAGCACCGGGGGGUCGGAGCCCAGGUUUCUGCUUUUCCUGGCUUCCAGCCAGGCUCCGAGUCCUAUAUGUCACUUGCUGGUCACUUGCUGUGUGCCAGGCCCUACUUGGGCCCCCUUGCCACAGCCCCAUGCAGCAUCAUCAGAGAGGCUGCAGCUGGCCCAAAGUGGCACAGCCAGGGACUGGACGGGAGCCGGGUGGGCGGUGUGUCCCCAGCUCCCCUGCUGCCCUGUGGGUGUGACCAGAGCGAGGCACCGCCUGUGAGUGGAGAUUGGGGCUGGGGGGCCUGUGGCAGGGACUUUUGCAUUCUCUUCUCCCCGUAACUGCUUCCCGCCCCACAUCCUCUUCUGGCUUUUGGAAUUUGACCCCAGAUCUAUAAGAAGAGCCUGGCUCCUCCCUCUCCCUCACCUCCUACACCGCCUCCAGGUUCUGCCACUUUUACAAAUUUGCUUUAUCUGUUCACUCUUUCCCUUCUCUCCAUCCCCGUGGCUCCAGCCGCGGCCUCAUCCUCUACCCCCGGACCCCUGGCGCAGCUCCUCCCUGGCCUCCAGCCGCGCCGCUCCAGUCCACUCAGAGGGGUCCUUCACCCACCAGAGCUGAGCCUGCCCCUCUGUUGUCACAGCCCGUUGUGAGAGGAAGGAGGGCCCCCCCGCCCCCGGCCCAUUGCCACGGCCUCUGUAACAGCUCGACAUUCCCUCCUCCCGGCUUCCCUCCUGGACGUUCCGGGGCCCACCCUGUGCCCGCCCUCUCACUUAGCCCUCGGACGGCUCCCCCACCCCCACACUUGCCUCCCUAGAGACCCAGGGCUCCUUGCCUCGGGUGCCAGCAGAGGAACUGCCGGUAGGGGGCGCUGGCUCGCUCGUUCCUGCAGCAAAUACUGAGGCUCGGAGGGGCCAGCGCCGUUGGCCGGCCUUGAGGAUGCAGCCGUGGACGCCGCGGCAAAGCCCUCAGGGGCUCCCCUCUUAGCAGGAAGGCAGGCAAUGAACGCAGGAACAAAUCACCGAGCAUCAGGUGCUGGGUGGCCGUGACACGAGCUGUGAAGAAAAGGAAGUGCAAGGGAUACGGACGCCCCCCAGCGUCCACGCGGAGCAUGAACAUUGAGGAUGGCGCGUGCCCGCGGCUCCCCGUGCCCCCCGCUGCCGCCCGGUAGGAUGUCCUGGCCCCACGGGGCAUUGCUCUUCCUCUGGCUCUUCUCCCCACCCCUGGGGGCCGGUGGAGGUGGAGUGGCCGUGACGUCUGCCGCCGGAGGGGGCUCCCCGCCGGCCACCUCCUGCCCCGUGGCCUGCUCCUGCAGCAACCAGGCCAGCCGGGUGAUCUGCACACGGAGAGACCUGGCCGAGGUCCCAGCCAGCAUCCCGGUCAACACGCGGUACCUGAACCUGCAAGAGAACGGCAUCCAGGUGAUCCGGACGGACACGUUCAAGCACCUGCGGCACCUGGAGAUUCUGCAGCUGAGCAAGAACCUGGUGCGCAAGAUCGAGGUGGGCGCCUUCAACGGGCUGCCCAGCCUCAACACGCUGGAGCUUUUUGACAACCGGCUGACCACGGUGCCCACGCAGGCCUUCGAGUACCUGUCCAAGCUGCGGGAGCUCUGGCUGCGGAACAACCCCAUCGAGAGCAUCCCCUCCUACGCCUUCAACCGCGUGCCCUCGCUGCGGCGCCUGGACCUGGGCGAGCUCAAGCGGCUGGAAUACAUCUCGGAGGCGGCCUUCGAGGGGCUGGUCAACCUGCGCUACCUCAACCUGGGCAUGUGCAACCUCAAGGACAUCCCCAACCUGACGGCCCUGGUGCGCCUGGAGGAGCUGGAGCUGUCGGGCAACCGGCUGGACCUGAUCCGCCCGGGCUCCUUCCAGGGUCUCACCAGCCUGCGCAAGCUGUGGCUCAUGCACGCCCAGGUAGCCACCAUCGAGCGCAACGCCUUCGACGACCUCAAGUCGCUGGAGGAGCUCAACCUGUCCCACAACAACCUGAUGUCGCUGCCCCACGACCUCUUCACGCCCCUGCACCGCCUCGAGCGCGUGCACCUCAACCACAACCCCUGGCAUUGCAACUGCGACGUGCUCUGGCUGAGCUGGUGGCUCAAGGAGACGGUGCCCAGCAACACGACGUGCUGCGCCCGCUGUCAUGCGCCCGCCGGCCUCAAGGGGCGCUACAUUGGGGAGCUGGACCAGUCGCAUUUCACCUGCUAUGCGCCCGUCAUCGUGGAGCCGCCCACGGACCUCAACGUCACCGAGGGCAUGGCUGCCGAGCUCAAAUGCCGCACGGGCACCUCCAUGACCUCCGUCAACUGGCUGACGCCCAACGGCACCCUCAUGACCCACGGCUCCUACCGCGUGCGCAUCUCCGUCCUGCAUGACGGCACGCUUAACUUCACCAACGUCACCGUGCAGGACACGGGCCAGUACACGUGCAUGGUGACGAACUCAGCCGGCAACACCACCGCCUCGGCCACGCUCAACGUCUCGGCCGUGGACCCCGUGGCGGCCGGGGGCACCGGCAGCGGCGGGGGCGGCCCUGGGGGCAGUGGUGGUGUUGGAGGGGGCAGUGGCGGCUACACCUACUUCACCACGGUGACCGUGGAGACCCUGGAGACGCAGCCCGGAGAGGAGGCCCUGCAGCCGCGGGGGACGGAGAAGGAACCGCCAGGGCCCACGACAGACGGUGUCUGGGGUGGGGGCCGGCCUGGGGACGCGGCCGGCCCUGCCUCGUCUUCUACCACGGCACCCGCCCCGCGCUCCUCGCGGCCCACGGAGAAGGCGUUCACGGUGCCCAUCACGGAUGUGACGGAGAACGCCCUCAAGGACCUGGACGACGUCAUGAAGACCACCAAAAUCAUCAUCGGCUGCUUCGUGGCCAUCACGUUCAUGGCCGCGGUGAUGCUCGUGGCCUUCUACAAGCUGCGCAAGCAGCACCAGCUCCACAAGCACCACGGGCCCACGCGCACCGUGGAGAUCAUCAACGUGGAGGACGAGCUGCCCGCCGCCUCGGCCGUGUCCGUGGCCGCCGCGGCCGCCGUGGCCAGUGGGGGUGGUGUGGGCGGGGACAGCCACCUGGCCCUGCCCGCCCUGGAGCGAGACCACCUCAACCACCACCACUACGUGGCUGCCGCCUUCAAGGCGCACUACAGCAGCAACCCCAGCGGCGGGGGCUGCGGGGGCAAAGGCCCGCCUGGCCUCAACUCCAUCCACGAACCUCUGCUCUUCAAGAGCGGCUCCAAGGAGAACGUGCAAGAGACGCAGAUCUGAGGCGGCGGGGCCGGGCGGGCGAGGGGCGUGGAGCCCCCCACCCAGGUCCCAGCCCGGGCGCAGCCUGACCGGGACCCCUCCCUCCCACAGCCCAGCCCACCUUCUGGGACCACGCAGGGAAUUGGGGAGAGGUGGCUUCCAGCCCCAUCUGGGGCUCGGACCCCCAGUAAGGACAGGGUGGGGCUCCAGGAGCGGAGUCUCUGGGAUCCUCGCCUCACCCCCGCCAAUCCCCGGUGACGGGAGGGGACGUGGGACCCAGGAGAAGUGGCCUGAGUUCUCCGCGUUUCCUCCUCGCUCUCCCACCAAGCGUUCCGGGCCCGCCGCCUUCCAGGGGAGAGAGGAGCUUUCUCCAGGGGUGUCCUUUCCCCUCGGCCCCAAACACCUUCCUUUUACGGUUCAGUUUUUGCAGUUUGACGCCCGUCCCUCCCUCCCACUCCUCCGCCCUCAAAACUGAAGAGAUGGACACGUCGCCAGAGCUCCCGUCCCAGCGCCCGGCUCUGCUCCCGGCCGGCGGUCCCUGUCGUCGGCGCGGGGGGGAGCCUCCACCCGCCCCAGCCCCACCUGCCCCACAGACACUUUUGAUACUGAAGGGAGGUUUGCGUCAACGACUACCUGCUCUGUAAUUACUUUAAAAAAAAAACAUGGAAAAAGUAAAAAAAUAUUUUUUUUGGUCAUGAAA